AUCUAGGGGCUGCUGGGAAGAUGGCGGACUCGGUGGCUAGCCGAUGAGGAGGCCGCGGGGGGAACCCGGCCCCCGGGCCCCGAGACCGACUGAGGGAGCGACCUGCGCAGGGCCCGGGGAGUCAUGUAGGGGUGGCGCCUGCGGGGAGGGCUGCGGGAGGGCAGCGGGAGCUGGUGUUAGCGGCAGCGGCCACGGUCUCCUGGCGUCCCUGGGCCGGGGUGGGUGUUGGGGCCCCCGACUUCGCCGACUCCGCGCCAUCGCAAAGCGGUGCACUCGGGCUCCACGCGCGCCCUGCGAGGUGGGCGCUGCGUUUUCAUUUCACGGGUGAGGAGACUUAGAGAGACGAAGCCACUUGUCCAAGGUCACGCCGCUGGUGAGUGGGAGCGCCCAGCAUGGAACCCAGCACCGUCCAGCCGCGGAGCCCGCGUUCCACCCUCUGUGCCGCCGCCGCCUCCUGUGGGAGAGGGAGGUGGUCGGGAGAGUGCACGCCGGUGCCGCCUGGGCUCCAGACUGGGCGCGACCACUAACCCGGUUAAUGACCUCGGGCUUAACUUAACCCCUUCGCUGCUCUGGGCCUGCGUUUCUCCACCGGUGAAAUGAGGUAAUGCCAGCCCUGCCUACUCUUCAUGGGCGUGUAAGGAGCAUCAGAGAUGGUGCAUGUGGAAUUGCUUUGCAAGUAGUGCUGCGCUGAGCGCACUGAGGAUUAUGAUUGCUGUUUCAAAGGCGUGGAAGGAGGCAGAGGGGCGGGGUGGGGAAGAGGCCCAGAGCAGUCACAAAGGCUUGCUCUGACCACAGGCCCCCUAAAUGAGGAGUGAGGUAAGCAGUAGGUAGCAGGUCUUUCUCCCCUUUGGAGAAAACCUCACCCCCUUUUUUGGGCUGCCCCUCAGGGUCUCCAUCACCCAACUCCAUGCUUCGAGUCCUGCUCUCUGCUCAGACCUCCCCUGCUCGGCUGUCUGGCCUGCUGCUGAUCCCUCCAGUACAGCCCUGCUGUUUGGGGCCCAGCAAAUGGGGGGACCGGCCUGUUGGAGGAGGCCCCAGUGCAGGUCCUGUGCAAGGACUGCAGCGGCUUCUGGAACAGGCGAAGAGCCCUGGGGAGCUGCUGCGCUGGCUGGGCCAGAACCCCAGCAAGGUGCGCGCCCACCACUACUCGGUGGCGCUUCGUCGUCUGGGCCAGCUCUUGGGGUCUCGGCCACGGCCCCCUCCUGUGGAGCAGGUCACACUGCAGGACUUGAGUCAGCUCAUCAUCCGAAACUGCCCCUCCUUUGACAUUCACACCAUCCACGUGUGUCUGCACCUUGCAGUCUUACUUGGCUUUCCAUCUGAUGGUCCCCUGGUGUGUGCCCUGGAACAGGAGCGAAGGCUCCGCCUCCCUCCGAAGCCACCUCCCCCUUUGCAGCCCCUUCUCCGAGAGGCAAGGCCAGAGGAACUGACUCCCCACGUGAUGGUGCUCCUGGCCCAGCACCUGGCCCGGCACCGGUUGCGGGAGCCCCAGCUUCUGGAAGCCAUUGCCCACUUCCUGGUGGUUCAGGAAACGCAACUCAGCAGCAAGGUGGUACAGAAGUUGGUCCUGCCCUUUGGGCGACUGAACUACCUGCCCCUGGAACAGCAGUUUAUGCCCUGCCUUGAGAGGAUCCUGGCUCGGGAAGCAGGGGUGGCACCCCUGGCUACAGUCAACAUCUUGAUGUCACUGUGCCAACUGCGGUGCCUGCCCUUCAGAGCCCUGCACUUUGUUUUUUCCCCUGGCUUCAUCAACUACAUCAGUGGCACCCCUCAUGCUCUGAUUGUGCGUCGCUACCUCUCCCUGCUGGACACGGCCGUGGAGCUGGAGCUCCCAGGAUACCGGGGUCCCCGCCUUCCCCGAAGGCAGCAAGUGCCCAUCUUUCCCCAGCCUCUCAUCACCGACCGUGCCCGCUGCAAGUACAGUCACAAGGACAUAGUAGCUGAGGGGUUGCGCCAGCUGCUGGGGGAGGAGAAAUACCGCCAGGACCUGACUGUGCCUCCAGGCUACUGCACAGCUACCCUUCGAGGAACUGGAGUCCCAGAGAGGCCUGCCCCAGCUCAAGAGCUACCUGAGGCAGAAGCUCCAGGCCCUGGGCCUGCGCUGGGGGCCUGAAGGGGGCUGAGGGGUUGAUGUGGGGUUCAGGAUGGCCCCCCCAUGGGGGGUGGAUGAUUUGCACUUUGGUUCCCUGUGUUUUGAUUUCUCAUUAAAGUUCCUUUCCUUCCC